AUAUUGGAAAGGCGCCGCCGCCGCCUCCGCCUUGGAGCUCGGGGUGUUUCGGGGACUGCGGCCACAGGCAGGAAGGCGCUCCUCUCCUGCCCCGCCGACGCCCGGCCAGCCCGCUUCGCCCUGACCUGUUUCCUCAUGACUGCCCCCGGCCCUGCUGCCGACGGACGUCGCCCCGGCGUCCGGAUUUAACACGGAAACCCGGAUCGGAGGCCGCGCGGGGAGGAGGAGGGCGACCCGGUCGGUCCUGCGACCCUCUCGGCCCGGCUCGGCGCCUCGGCGGGAGCCAUGACCUCGCUGACCCAGCGCAGCUCCGGCCUGGUGCAGCGGCGCACCGAGGCCUCCCGCAACGCCGCCGACAAGGAGCGGGCGGCGGGCGGCGGCGCCGGCAGCAGCGAGGACGACGCGCAGAGCCGCCGCGACGAGCAGGACGACGACGACAAGGGCGACUCCAAGGAAACGCGGCUGACCCUGAUGGAGGAAGUGCUCCUGCUGGGCCUCAAGGACCGCGAGGGUUACACAUCAUUUUGGAAUGACUGUAUAUCAUCUGGAUUACGUGGCUGUAUGUUAAUUGAAUUAGCAUUGAGAGGAAGGUUACAACUAGAGGCUUGUGGAAUGAGACGUAAAAGUCUAUUAACAAGAAAGGUAAUCUGUAAGUCAGAUGCUCCAACAGGGGAUGUUCUUCUUGAUGAAGCUCUGAAGCAUGUUAAGGAAACUCAGCCUCCAGAAACGGUCCAGAACUGGAUUGAAUUACUUAGUGGUGAGACAUGGAAUCCAUUAAAAUUGCAUUAUCAGUUAAGAAAUGUACGGGAACGAUUAGCUAAAAACCUGGUGGAAAAGGGUGUAUUGACAACAGAGAAACAGAACUUCCUACUUUUUGACAUGACAACACAUCCCCUCACCAAUAACAACAUUAAGCAGCGCCUCAUCAAGAAAGUACAGGAAGCCGUUCUUGACAAAUGGGUGAAUGACCCUCACCGCAUGGACAGGCGCUUGCUGGCCCUCAUUUACCUGGCUCAUGCCUCGGACGUCCUGGAGAAUGCUUUUGCUCCUCUUCUGGACGAGCAGUAUGAUUUGGCUACCAAGAGAGUGCGGCAGCUUCUCGACUUAGACCCUGAAGUGGAAUGUCUGAAGGCCAACACCAAUGAGGUUCUGUGGGCGGUGGUGGCGGCGUUCACCAAGUAACUCUGCUCGGGGUGAACCAUUCUCCUUUCUCUCAAGUAAACCAGUAGUUUUUCUUCUGUUGACUUCUGGUUUUCUGUAAUUUGUACUUUCCCACACUAUAAUUGGCUUCUGUUUUACAAAAUGGUGGGUGGCUUUUUCUUUUUUGUACGUGUACAGGAUUCUGCUGGUACGAGAGGCCUUCCUCUUUCUGUUUUUAAAAAAAGUUUUACUGCCAUAUUGGCAUUCCAUUCCCUGUUGCCAUCCUCACUGUUACCUGUUUUGGGUUUCUGGUCUACUUUGACUUUCAAAGUACCUCCAGCCUCCUCAUACGCACAGCUUUUGGAUGACCUCAGCUUGAGUUUCUCCAUAUGUGCAUGUACAUCUAGCAUUCUGCCUACAGUUCAGACAGAAGUCACAAAAAGGCCUUCAACUCACCAAAGGUAAAUAUCUGUAUCUAUUAGGACAUUUUUUACAUAGACUUCAGUUGAGAUGUAUACUUAGCAAAAUUAUUUUUAAAUUGAAACAGCACAGUAAAUACUUAAUAUAAAAUGUCCCUUGGAUUUUGCUUCCCAUGUAAAUCUAUUGUAUUAUUACACUUGUUAUAAUUUUAACUAUAAAGGUCCAAUUGUUUCACAGAGCCAGUUUGGGAUGGGCUGCAUUCCAUUUAUGCUGUAUAUAGUUUGAAUUAUAUAUAAAUUACCCCUUCUUCUGGCCACCCCUGCUCCCAUCUUAGUAUUUUGCAAGAUCUAAUCAGUUGUACACCUGGUGCCCCUCGCUUGCUUCAAUCAUGGUUAUUUGAUGGCAAAAUCGACCUCUUGUCGCUGAAGGAGAGAGAAAAGAUGUGUGUCUGAUUGGUCCUGGGAUUUUUUGAGCUGUGCCAUUUAUGGUACUCUUUGCCUAUGCAUCCCCUUGUUAGAUUUUUUUUAAAUUUUAUCUUACUGUUUUUAUAAUUUCUAUUGGGAAGAGGCUUGUGACCAGUACCAAUCUUGAGUUUCUUUUUCUGUCCACAAGUAAAUUAAUAUCUGCUCUGAAAUGUCAUUUAUCUACUCACACAUUCUUGGGGAAAAAAAUCAAAUGUCAGUCCUAGCAGAUGUUGCAUGUAAAUUGGUAGCAAGUAAUGAUUACAACCCAGAGGAUUAAGAAUUUUGUAACAGAAAGCUCUAUGUUUUAAUUUUUUAUAUACAAUUAGGAUAAUUAGCAUUGUCAGACUAUAAACCUUUGCUUUUUAAAGUUUAUUUUUACUAUUUCUUUAUCACUUUAUUGUAUCAUCACCAUUGGUUUCAUAAUGUAAAUACUAUAUGUUGAACAAAUUAAAUGUCAAAAUUUUUUAUUACCAUAGUCCAUGUUAAUAGUGGGGCUUUCAGGUGUUUAGAGAUUUUUUUUGUUGUUGUUAACAUUCAUUGCAAAAGUACUAGAUGGUGUAUAACUCUAGAGUUGAAUUUUAAGGGAUUCCCUAAUAUGUAUACUAUCUUUUUAUCUGAAGUAAUAAAUAAACAAUGAUCUUGAAAGUGCCUGAA